CUUUUUCGCAACGGGUUUGCCGCCAGAACACAGGUGUCGUGAAAACUACCCCUAAAAGCCAAAAUGGGAAAGGAAAAGACUCAUAUCAACAUUGUCGUCAUUGGACACGUAGAUUCGGGCAAGUCCACCACUACUGGCCAUCUGAUCUAUAAAUGCGGUGGCAUCGACAAAAGAACCAUUGAAAAAUUUGAGAAGGAGGCUGCUGAGAUGGGAAAGGGCUCCUUCAAGUAUGCCUGGGUCUUGGAUAAACUGAAAGCUGAGCGUGAACGUGGUAUCACCAUUGAUAUCUCCUUGUGGAAAUUUGAGACCAGCAAGUACUAUGUGACUAUCAUUGAUGCCCCAGGACACAGAGACUUUAUCAAAAACAUGAUUACAGGGACAUCUCAGGCUGACUGUGCUGUCCUGAUUGUUGCUGCUGGUGUUGGUGAAUUUGAAGCUGGUAUCUCCAAGAAUGGGCAGACCCGAGAGCAUGCCCUUCUGGCUUACACACUGGGUGUGAAACAACUAAUUGUCGGUGUUAACAAAAUGGAUUCCACUGAGCCACCCUACAGCCAGAAGAGAUAUGAGGAAAUUGUUAAGGAAGUCAGCACUUACAUUAAGAAAAUUGGCUACAACCCCGACACAGUAGCAUUUGUGCCAAUUUCUGGUUGGAAUGGUGACAACAUGCUGGAGCCAAGUGCUAACAUGCCUUGGUUCAAGGGAUGGAAAGUCACCCGUAAGGAUGGCAAUGCCAGUGGAACCACGCUGCUUGAGGCUCUGGACUGCAUCCUACCACCAACUCGUCCAACUGACAAGCCCUUGCGCCUGCCUCUCCAGGAUGUCUACAAAAUUGGUGGUAUUGGUACUGUUCCUGUUGGCCGAGUGGAGACUGGUGUUCUCAAACCCGGUAUGGUGGUCACCUUUGCUCCAGUCAACGUUACAACGGAAGUAAAAUCUGUCGAAAUGCACCAUGAAGCUUUGAGUGAAGCUCUUCCUGGGGACAAUGUGGGCUUCAAUGUCAAGAAUGUGUCUGUCAAGGAUGUUCGUCGUGGCAACGUUGCUGGUGACAGCAAAAAUGACCCACCAAUGGAAGCAGCUGGCUUCACUGCUCAGGUGAUUAUCCUGAACCAUCCAGGCCAAAUAAGCGCCGGCUAUGCCCCUGUAUUGGAUUGCCACACGGCUCACAUUGCAUGCAAGUUUGCUGAGCUGAAGGAAAAGAUUGAUCGCCGUUCUGGUAAAAAGCUGGAAGAUGGCCCUAAAUUCUUGAAGUCUGGUGAUGCUGCCAUUGUUGAUAUGGUUCCUGGCAAGCCCAUGUGUGUUGAGAGCUUCUCAGACUAUCCACCUUUGGGUCGCUUUGCUGUUCGUGAUAUGAGACAGACAGUUGCGGUGGGUGUCAUCAAAGCAGUGGACAAGAAGGCUGCUGGAGCUGGCAAGGUCACCAAGUCUGCCCAGAAAGCUCAGAAGGCUAAAUGAAUAUUAUCCCUAAUACCUGCCACCCCACUCUUAAUCAGUGGUGGAAGAACGGUCUCAGAACUGUUUGUUUCAAUUGGCCAUUUAAGUUUAGUAGUAAAAGACUGGUUAAUGAUAACAAUGCAUCGUAAAACCUUCAGAAGGAAAGGAGAAUGUUUUGUGGACCACUUUGGUUUUCUUUUUUGCGUGUGGCAGUUUUAAGUUAUUAGUUUUUAAAAUCAGUACUUUUUAAUGGAAACAACUUGACCAAAAAUUUGUCACAGAAUUUUGAGACCCAUUAAAAAAGUUAAAUGAGAAACCUGUGUGUUCCUUUGGUCAACACCGAGACAUUUAGGUGAAAGACAUCUAAUUCUGGUUUUACGAAUCUGGAAACUUCUUGAAAAUGUAAUUCUUGAGUUAACACUUCUGGGUGGAGAAUAGGGUUGUUUUCCCCCCACAUAAUUGGAAGGGGAAGGAAUAUCAUUUAAAGCUAUGGGAGGGUUGCUUUGAUUACAACACUGGAGAGAAAUGCAGCAUGUUGCUGAUUGCCUGUCACUAAAACAGGCCAAAAACUGAGUCCUUGUGUUGCAUAGAAAGCUUCAUGUUGCUAAACCAAUGUUAAGUGAAUCUUUGGAAACAAAAUGUUUCCAAAUUACUGGGAUGUGCAUGUUGAAACGUGGGUUAAAAUGACUGGGCAGUGAAAGUUGACUAUUUGCCAUGACAUAAGAAAUAAGUGUAGUGGCUAGUGUACACCCUAUGAGUGGAAGGGUCCAUUUUGAAGUCAGUGGAGUAAGCUUUAUGCCAGUUUGAUGGUUUCACAAGUUCUAUUGAGUGCUAUUCAGAAUAGGAACAAGGUUCUAAUAGAAAAAGAUGGCAAUUUGAAGUAGCUAUAAAAUUAGACUAAUCUACAUUGCUUUUCUCCUGCAGAGUCUAAUACCUUUUAUGCUUUGAUAAUUAGCAGUUUGUCUACUUGGUCACUAGGAAUGAAACUACAUGGUAAUAGGCUUAACAGGUGUAAUAGCCCACUUACUCCUGAAUCUUUAAGCAUUUGUGCAUUUGAAAAAUGCUUUUCGCGAUCUUCCUGCUGGGAUUACAGGCAUGAGCCACUGUGCCUGACCUCCCAUAUGUAAAAGUGUCUAAAGGUUUUUUUUUGGUUAUAAAAGGAAAAUUUUUGCUUAAGUUUGAAGGAUAGGUAAAAUUAAAGGACAUGCUUUCUGUUUGUGUGAUGGUUUUUAAAAAUUUUUUUUAAGAUGGAGUUCUUGUUGCCCAGGCUAGAAUGCAAUGGCAAAAUCUCACUGCAAUCUCCUCCUCCUGGGUUCAAGCAAUUCUCCUACUUCAGCCUCCCAAGUAGCUGGGAUUACAGGCAUGUGCUAAUUUGGUGUUUUUAAUAGAGAUGAGGUUUUUCCAUGUUGGUCAGGCUGGUCUCAAACUCCUGACCUUAGGUGAUCGCCUCGGCCUCCUAAAGUGCUGGAAUUACAGGCAUGAGCCACCAUGCCUGGCCAGGACAUGUGUUCUUAAGGACAUGCUAAGCAGGAGUUAAAGCAGCCCAAGAGAUAAGGCCUCUUAAAGUGACUGGCAAUGUGUAUUGCUCAAGAUUCAAAGGUACUUGAAUUGGCCAUAGACAAGUCUGUAAUGAAGUGUUAUCGUUUUCCCUCAUCUGAGUCUGAAUUAGAUAAAAUGCCUUCCCAUCAGCCAGUGCUCUGAGGUAUCAAGUCUAAAUUGAACUAGAGAUUUUUGUCCUUAGUUUCUUUGCUAUCUAAUGUUUACACAAGUAAAUAGUCUAAGAUUUGCUGGAUGACAGAAAAAACAGGUAAGGCCUUUAAUAGAUGGCCAAUAGAUGCCCUGAUAAUGAAAGUUGACACCUGUAAGAUUUACCAGUAGAGAAUUCUUGACAUGCAAGGAAGCAAGAUUUAACUGAAAAAUUGUUCCCACUGGAAGCAGGAAUGAGUCAGUUUACUUGCAUAUACUGAGAUUGAGAUUAACUUCCUGUGAAACCCAGUGUCUUAGACAACUGUGGCUUGAGCACCACCUGCUGGUAUUCAUUACAAACUUGCUCACUACAAUAAAUGAAUUUUAAGCUUUAA